GCUGCCUCCUCUGACUGUUAUGCAGCAGGCCGGCAGGUCAAUAAACUUGCUUGCCUGACUUUGAGUAUACUCGUCUUUUCUCUUGGCCAACCUUACGGUAGCUGUACCAGUUUGCAUUUCCACCAGCAAUGAAUGAGAGUUCCUGUUGCUCUGCAUCCUCACCAGCAUUUGGUGUGGUCAGUAUUUUGGAUUUUCACCAUUCUAAUAGAGAUUCACGGAUCCAUCCGGGUGGUCCGGGCACCACUGGCGCCCCUCUGCGGCUAUUCCCCAGUUCCAUUUUCUGAAGCCACAGGUCAGAAGCCGCUGUACAACGCUUUGCCGAACUCCAGAAUCUUGAAGGAGACGUAAGGUGCAGCCACCUGCCGCGCAGGCGCAAGCCUUUCUUUCGGCACAAAGACCGUGGGAGGAGGGGUCGGCGCAAGCGCUCGGUGUCUCUCUGAAAAGAACUUCAUCAUACUGCCUCCUGGCUGACGGAGCGCAGCGCAACGCAUGCGCCUUGAAGACUUAUGGAACUUAUUUCACGCUCAGGGCGGCGGUGACGUGUGAACGAGAAGGAGGUGGUCAAGGAACGGAAGCCGGGAGGGAACGAGGGCGGAAGCGGACCAGGGCCAGGCUUGUGUUCGCAGCCUUGCCGGGGCUGGGGUUCCGAUGUGGUCCCCGGAGCGGGAGGCCGAGGCCCCAGCCGGGGGAGACCCGGCGGGCCUUCUGCCCCCCGAGUGGGAGGAGGACGAGGAGCGCAUGUCCUUCCUGUUCUCCGCUUUCAAGAGGAGUCGCGAGGUGAACAGCACCGACUGGGACAGCAAGAUGGGCUUCUGGGCGCCGUUGGUGCUGAGCCACAGCCGCCGCCAGGGGGUGGUGCGCCUGCGUCUGCGGGACUUGCAGGAGGCCUUUCAGCGCAAGGGGAGCGUCCCGCUGGGGCUGGCCACGGUGCUGCAGGACCUGCUGCGUCGAGGGGAGCUGCAGCGGGAGUCAGACUUCAUGGCCAGUGUAGACAGCAGCUGGAUCUCCUGGGGGGUUGGGGUCUUCCUGCUGAAGCCUCUCAAGUGGACUCUUUCUAACAUGCUGGGAGAUAAUAAGGUUCCAGCUGAGGAGGUCCUUGUCGCUGUGGAGCUGUUGAAGGAAAAGGCUGAGGAGGUGUAUCGUCUGUAUCAGAACUCGCCCCUCUCCUCCCACCCCGUGGUGGCCCUGUCAGAGCUCAGCACCCUCUGUGCUAACUCCUGCCCAGAUGAGAGGACCUUCUACUUGGUGUUGCUGCAGCUGCAGAAGGAGAAGAGGGUCACAGUCCUCGAGCAGAACGGGGAGAAGAUUGUGAAGUUUGCCCGAGGGCCACGUGCCAAGGUCUCUCCAGUCAAUGACGUAGAUGUUGGGGUGUACCAGCUGAUGCAGAGUGAACAGCUUCUCUCACGCAAAGUGGAGUCCUUAUCCCAGGAAGCAGAGAGGUGUAAAGAAGAAGCCCGCCGGGCAUGCCGAGCAGGAAAGAAGCAGCUGGCACUGAGGUCUCUCAAGGCCAAGCAACGGACAGAGAAGCGCAUCGAGGCCUUGCAUGCCAAGCUGGACACUGUUCAAGGCAUCCUGGACCGGAUCUAUGCCUCCCAGACAGAUCAGAUGGUUUUUAACGCCUACCAGGCUGGGGUAGGAGCACUCAAACUCUCCAUGAAGGAUGUCACAGUGGAGAAGGCAGAGAGCCUCGUGGAUCAGAUCCAAGAGCUCUGUGACACCCAGGAUGAAGUUUCUCAGACUCUGGCUGGUGGGGUAACAAAUGGCUUAGAUUUUGACAGUGAAGAACUGGAGAAGGAAUUGGACAUCCUCCUUCAGGAUACCACCAAAGAACCUUUGGAUCUGCCUGACAACCCCCGCAAUAGGCAUUUUACCAACAGCGUGCCUAACCCUAGGAUCUCAGAUGCUGAACUUGAAGCUGAACUUGAGAAACUGUCCUUAUCAGAGGGAGGUUUGGUCCCAAGCAGUAAAUCUCCAAAAAGGCAAUUGGAACCGACUCUAAAGCCAUUGUAGGACCCUCAAGUGAAGGACCCUCAUGUAAAAGAGAGACCAGGCUUGCUGGGUGUGUACAUAGUUAUUUAAACAAGAAACUCUCAGAAUGUGUUUGGAAGAGGAGAAAGGAGAACCACUGAUUUUAUCUGGAUGCUACUACUUACUACAGGACAGAUAGAAUUUCUGGAAGCGAUGCUCCAAAGGCUUGCUCCCAGCUGUAUCAUGGACCUGCCUUCUCAUCUUUAUAGUGCCACGAUUUAUACAGUCCUGUGUCUGACCUGUCAUUUCAUAGCCUGCAGUUCUUGCCAUUGGCACACUUAGAUUUGUCUUCACCCACCAGCUUCGUUCCAGCCCAUGAAGGGGAAAGAUUUGCAGCUUUGCCAAAUCUGAAUCAGUUCCCACUCCCCCCUGCGGUUUUUUAGAGGGGUUUAUCCUGUCGCUAAUGUCAGUUAAAUAGCUUAUUCCUGUCCCACUUGAUUUCACUGGUAAGAAUGAGAAUGAAAUACUUAAAGGUUUUAUUUGAGGGGACUUAGCUGCCAUUUUAUGGAAAAACAUGUAGUAUAAAAGGUUUUUCUCCAGGGUCAUUUGACAGAAUUCUCCAGGUGUUCAGAGAAAGAGGUCGCCCCAAGUGGCCCAGAGUCGUGACAGUCCGGAGGGGCUGGUGUGGCCGGUGGGCGCUGCCUCUUCAUCUGAUGGAGCCAGGAGGUCCGCCGGUGGGGGAAAGGCUUCUUCCGAGGCUUCUGCACUCGCCUGGGAAGAGGCCCAGUCACUACAGGACCCUGAGAUGUCCAGACCCCUUAUGCAAAGAGGCAAAAUUGUUGCCUUGGCCCCAUCAUGGAGUAACUUAAAAAUACAUAUCUAUCUUCCAGAACAAGCCACACAACAACACACCUCCCCUCCUUGAGCCUGGCACACAGCACCGGGCUCUCUGAAUUUGGAAAGUGUUUCAUUUUGUGGCCUACUGCUCGGGGCAGGGGGGCUGAGCCAGGAUGUGCAAUAGAAGCAGGGGUUGUCCCCUCUGCCAGAUCUGUGGGGAGCUGCCCAGGCCACCCGUGCACCUGUCCUGCUUCCUGCAGUCCCCACUCCCUGCCUCCUUUGAGGGACUGGGGGACUUGGGGUAGGGGGACAGACGGGAAAGGGUCUGAAUGCUCUGGCAAUGGCGAGAAGAAGCGAUCGCCACACUGCCACUCUGCUGCCCAGCCACCAGGAUUUCUGCCUGGAGCCCUUUGCCCUGUCCCUGCUGCCUGAGGUGGCGUAGAGCAGAGGAGAAGAAUUUGCUCCAGGCCAGGAGCACAAAUCGUUGUUCAAUGAAUUUCUCUCCAACUCGACCUUGGUAAACGGAAAUGUUGGGGGUGAAGAGAAACAAUCACUAUUUUUUUCUUUUUUAUCUGGUAAAUAAUUAAAAGAAAAACCGAACACUU